AGUGUUGCCAUCGGCGUGCGCGCGUGUGUGCGAGUGUGACAGCGGCUGUGGCUGUGGCCGUGGCCGUGGGAGGCGGGCCCGGCGGAGCCCAGCCGCGGGGGGACCGGCCCGGGCUCCCGCUCCCCGAGCGCGUCGCGGCCGCGUGGCCCAGCCGAGCCUUGAGACCACCCCGCCCCUGCCGGUCGCAGUCGCGAUGUCGGUGGCCGGGCUGAAGAAGCAGUUCCACAAAGCCAGCCAGGAGCUUUUAAGUGAAUAAGACCAUUUUCCCAAUGAGCAGUGUCAUAAACAUUGAGGACUCUCUUAAAUCAGAAGAUGAAUGAAUGGAUGGAAUCUUUGCUGGGAUAAUAUGCAAUCAAGCUAAUAGGUGCCUUACCUGGACCUCCCAACAGCUAUUUAGUGAAAAAAUAAGUGGUGCUGAAGGAACUAAACUAGACGAUGAAUUUCUUGACAUGGAAAGGAAAAUAGAUGUUACCAAUAAAGUUGUUGCAGAAAUUCUUUCAAAAACCACUGAAUAUCUUCAGCCAAAUCCAGCAUACAGAGCUAAGCUAGGAAUGCUGAACACUGUGUCGAAGAUCCGAGGGCAGGUGAAGACCACAGGAUACCCGCAGACGGAAGGCUUGCUGGGGGACUGUAUGCUGAAAUACGGGAAGGAGCUCGGGGAAGACUCCACCUUUGGCAAUGCAUUGAUAGAAGUUGGUGAAUCCAUGAAGCUAAUGGCUGAGGUGAAAGACUCUCUUGAUAUUAAUGUAAAGCAAACUUUUAUUGAUCCACUUCAGUUACUACAAGAUAAAGAUUUAAAAGAGAUCGGGCAUCACCUGAAAAAGCUGGAAGGCCGCCGCCUGGAUUACGAUUAUAAAAAGAAACGAGUAGGUAAGAUACCAGACGAAGAAGUCAGACAAGCGGUAGAAAAAUUUGAAGAGUCAAAGGAGUUGGCUGAAAGAAGCAUGUUUAACUUUUUAGAAAAUGAUUUGUGAAAGAGAAUGGCUUGUCGUCUUUUGAAGAUGUACACUUCUUUAUUCCUGCAUGCCAAACACACUUGCAGACCCCAGGCGUCUGGACAGGCAUCAGCUACUCACAUCACAGUUCUCUCUCUGUCCUCGCCAUGGGCUUCAGGGUGUGCUACUCUCUGCUUACUCACCCGGCUGCUCACCAAGUCCCCUGGUAAGGGAUUGCUAAAGGGUCAGAGGAGGAGGGUUCCCAGCCCUGCUCCUUCUAGGCACCCCAGUUUCCAUAGUCCUCUUGCAGAGUUGGCCUAAGACAGCCUUGGUUACAGUAUGCAGUCCUUUGAGCCAUUCUUCCUUUGGGUACAGCCUAAGCCUUUUGCAGUUGGCUCACAAGGCCAGGCCAAUGGCUCAGAUCUUAUGCAAGUGUCCCUGGGGUUUCCAUAACUCCUAGAAACUUCUAGUAUCCUUAGUCCAUUGUAGUUGGGGACAUCUAUUCUCUGUUUCCAUCCCCAGGACUAAGAUACUCCCAACGGCCAUAUAUGCUGCUAAUCAUCCAUUGGUUUCCAGCUAUAGAGAGGUUUGGAAUGAAAUGCAUCCACAGGUGACACACGUGUGUCACUUGUGGAUUGUUUAUUGUGUAUAGUCUGCCAUGGGAGAUAAAUUGAGUUAAUUCCUGUUUUGGGGUUAUCCCUCAGAAGAGAGUGAGGAGCCCUGGGAUACAGCCAAACCAACAAUGAAGUCCCCAGGCCCAGCCACGAUGGGCCCAUUACCCCCUGAGCUUGGUUCUUAUGCGUCUCCAGGCAACAACUCCCAUCACCAUGAAUGGGGGUCCCUGGGCAGCACUAAUCUCAUUGUUAGGUUUUUGCAUAGUUUGAGGAUGGGCUAAAGCAGCUCUGUAUCAGUUUCCUAUUGGGGCCAUAACAAAUGACCACAAACUGUAGCUUAAAGCAACACACAUUUAUUGUCUUCCAGCCUAGAGUCCUAAAAUCAAGGUGUGGGUAGGGCCAUGUUUGUUCUGGAGGCUCUUGAGGAAGAAGCUGCUUCUUUGCCUUUUCCAGCUUCUACAGGCCACCUGCAUUUCUUGGCUCAUUCUUCGCUUCCUCCCUCUUCACAGCCAGCGGCACAGCAUCUUCACGUAUCUCAUUCUGACCUCUGCUUCCAUUGUCAUAUCUUCUCUGACCUUGGCACUCCUGUCUCCCCCUUAAAGGACCUCGUGAUUACAUUGAGCCAUUCAGACGUUCCAAAAUAAUCUCUUCAUGUUAAGAUCCUUAACUCAAUCAUAACCGCAAAGUCCCUUUUGCUAUGUAAAGUAACAUAUUUGCAGGUUUGGGGAAUUAAUAUUUGGACAUCUUUGCAGGUUCCAUGAUUCUGUCUACCUCAGGCCCCCUCUGGUUUUAUGGUUCUGUGUGUCUCCCAAGUUGCUUCUUCACAGCCCUCACUUCACACAUUUGUCAACCACCGAGGCCUGUGCCUCCUUGACCUCUAACCUACAUGGAAGUCAGCUUGCAUUAUGAGUUUCUCACUUCAAACAUCAGCUGAGUGUGAGCCCAUCUGUAGGAGCUAGAGUGCUUCACUUUCAGAAAAGGGAGUGGAUUCUCUGGAAAUCCAGUUCCUUGGCGUAUAUCACGUGAACAUUUUCAUGGGUGAGGUCACACUUUGCUCUCAAGAUGGCACCAGCACAGUGUCAGCCCAGGUCUCAACCCGGAAGUGGAAUUAAACCUUUCUUCCCACCCCAGGUGACUUUCUCUGAUUCAACAGAUGGACUGCUGAAAUUCCAACAAUGGAAGAAAUGUUUUACCUUUUGGUCAGGUUUUGGCUCUUGCUAAGCCUGAGUUUGUUGCUUUAUCUUGGUUCUGCCUGUCUAGGUAUUUAUUUCUAAUCGUGGUUCAGGAAGCUGAAUGUACCUGUGUUGGUCCCCAUGGUCCCCAGCACACAGCUCAAUGCUCAUGACCUGGGGGACAGCUGGAAGCUUCAAUUUUCUGAAAUCAAGAGGAAAAUAAUCUAUCGUAGCACACCUGGUCUUUACUGUCAACAAGAGACUUACAGCCUAGUAGCCAGCCCUUCAGGACUUGUACUGAGCACCUGCUAGGUGCAAGCAUUGGGCAGUGCUGCCAUUGUUUCCCAAGGUUUAAGGGUUUUCAGGAUUCAUUUCCUUCCCAAAGUCAGCCACCCAAUGAGCAGUUACGAAUGCAUCUCUAGAUUACAUCACCUUGUGUUUUAGCCACGACAGGGAGGAUAGCUGGUAAUCCCCUUGCCCCCUUCCUGUUCCCCAACCCCAAAUAUGUUUCAAGAAAUAUUAAUUUAGCUAUCUUUCACUAUUUCUUUAAAAAUUAUAAAAUGCAAGCAUUUUUUAAAGUGGGUAAUAAGACAGGGCAAAUAAAUUUUACUAAAGGCAGAGAGGCAUAGCAUAGAUUUUGCCAAGCACACCACUCUAGCACUGUAAGGAAGAAAAAUUGUUUCUGUAACAAAUUCUACUACGAUCGUGCUAGGCCAUGGCCCUGGACUUAUUUAAAAGUACGUGUAAAAGCCAAAGAGAUGAAAUUUAAGAAAUCCUUAGGAUUUAGUAGGGGCCAGGCUGUCUUUGUUUUGUUUAUUGGGUUUUUGGAAAUUUAAGGCUAGGCUUGUUGCUUUUCCAGCCACAGAGCAUGGUAAAGUAAAUGAAACCCGACAGGAUUUCAUUGUUCGGAUGCUGAUCACAGCUUGGCACACAUGGAAUUCAAUGUGUCUCUUACAUGCAUAUUGAGCCCGUGUUUAAAAUAGUAUAAGUGAGUAAGAAAAAUUUAAGUACAGGCAACUAAAGAAUGAUUUGCAACUACAAAUGAAAGUAGCUUGGAUCUUUGAAGGCUAAGUCCAUGGUUGGUUAGGCAGGGUGAGAUUGCAUAAAUGAAUCAGCAGGCAGACUUUGCCCUAAAGCUGAGUAGAAAAUGAAGUAUGGAAAUGAUGCAUAGGCUUUGGGGAAGCCUGGGAAGUGUAGGAUUGAUUUUGAUUUGUGUCUUUGUCCAGCUCUAGAGUUGAUUGGAUUCUUGCUGGGGGAGGCCCAUCACCUCAACCCUCUGGAGCUUGCCUCUGGGGCUUUCAGAAAUAAGCUUAAUUAAUCUCUUUCCUGUAGCAGCCCCUCAGACACGUGGGGGAGCAGGAAAGCUCUCAGGCCUUCCUUAGAUUGCUUUUCCUCAAAUUAUACAGCCCCAUAUCAUCCAGGUUUUUCCUUAUGAGACACAGCUCUAAAAAAUUCAUUGUAAGUUAGUCAUUAAUUUCAUGAAUGUCUUGAUUUGUGGGAAACAGAGAUGCCAGUGUCUUUAUAGUUCAUUCCCUUUAGCUCUAUGUUUCAGGGAAAAUAUGUUGAGUGGAUAGCAACAAAACGCAUAGAGGGGACAGGGAAAUCUUUGCCCCAGUUCACAUGUUGCUCCCUGGCCCCCUUUCUUAUCUGUUUCAUUUACAGUUCUUAACUGUUUAAUGUACUUAAUGUCUUGAUUUGGCUUAGCUAGAAAGUGCGUGUUGAGACACUUGACAAAGUAGGCAGUUCUUUUGCUAAAUGUUGGCUUCGUUUGUAACUGGAAGAGCUUUAUCUCUCUGUUUUCAGAUCCAUGAGCUUUAUAGCAUAGAAAAUCUGCUGAGAAAAAUCAUCAUCUAAUUGGAAAAACAGGCAUUUUAUUGAGUUAAAUCAAAUUCAUAAUCACAAAUAAAUUUGAACAUGUUUUUCCAGCAUUUAUAGCUCCAUACCAUGACCUGUAUGAUUAUUAUACAGAGCUCCUACAUGAAAUUAAAUGAAAUGGACCAAGGCAGACACUGGUCUUCCCUGCAAAGCUAGGUCUUUGCUGCUGGUCUCCUCUCUCUCUGGACAUUACACAGGCUCGGGCCUCCAUGGAAUAAUUUUGCACUUCU